AAUACAAAAAAUACUUACUAAUUUUUUUCUUUUUUAACAGUCUAGGCUGAAAUUUACCUGUUUGAAAAAAAGGUUAGCUAAGCAAAUUUAUAAUACAAGCAGUAUUUCAUAAGACAUCUCUAAUUCUAUUUAAAAAUAAGCCAUAUCAAAAUGCAAAGAACAUUUAUUUGUAUACGUAAUAUUCUUGUAAAAGUAAGUGUACCGUUUUGCAGAUAGAGUGACUCUUUGUGCCUAAAAUGUAGUAGUUAUUGCUUUUUAAGUGAUUCAGAUUUUAUUCAGACUAACCUAAAUUUCAACCACUACCAAUAAAUUUGGGAUUUUCUUCUCUGUUAUUUUUCUCUUUCAGAACCAAUGGAGUUGUUAAUUAGCAGUGACAUGAUUUAAGAGACAAUAACCAGAAAAGAAAUAAGUAAAAACCACGUAGGAAACUUCUCUGUGAUUGAUCUGCACUCUUAAAUUGUAUUUAAGUAUGCGUGUGUCCUGUGGCAGUAGCUGCUCUAGUUUUAACACUGGCCUCUAUUUAAAAGGCAGCCUCAUCAAGAUACUUACAGUAUUUCUCAGCCAAGCACAGAAAUCAAAUAACGGUCCCUCCAGAUAACAGCCACAGACUUGAAUCCUAUGUAUAAUCUUAGUAACCCAAUAAAAUAACUUAUUUGAAGUAAACUCUAUUGGAUUAACAUACAGUUUCUAUAUGAAACUGGCCUCUUCAUUACAUUGUUUGCCACAGGCUUCUUAAUCUGUAAAGUCUGAAAAGAACAAUUUUUUGUUUUUACUGAAAAACAGUUUUAUGUUAAUAUUUGUUGUCCUGUAUGUUGUCUAUUAGUAGACUGGUUAUCCUUGAAAACAAAGACUUUGAUAGCUGUUUGUUAGUGUAAGUGGAUAAAAUGUGGAAUACUUCUGUAUUUAACAUAAAGUAAGCUUGUGAGUAGUUUAUAUUUCACCUGAUUAUACUUAAACUAUGAAAAUAUUAUCAGUAAAACUUUUAUUUAAAAGACACCUUAUUUCCAGAAUUAUUAAUGGCAUAGAUGCAUAACCAAGACAAAAAACAAAGGAAACAAAGAAGCUUUGCAGUCCCAAAUGAUAACAUGCAAUUUGGAUAAGGACAAAAGGGUUUUGUUUUGGUUUUCAGAAGAAGGAGGUUGUCAUUUUUGUUGCCUAUUUUAAGCUUCUGAUUUUAAAAAUAUUUAUAUUUUGUUUGUUAGCUUAUCUUAGAACUUGAAUUUUAAACUUAUAUAUCACUAUUGUGCUAUAAUAUAGGAAGCAAUAGAGUAUUACUAAUAUUCUUUUUUUUUUAGACAGAGUCUCACUUUGUCACCCAGGCUGGAGUGCAGUGGGGUGAUCUCAGCUCACUGCAACCUCUGCCUCCCGGGUUCAAGUGAUUCUUCUGCCUCAGCCUCCUGAGUAUCUGGGAUUACAGGUGUGCUACCAUGCCCAGCUAAUUUUUGUAUUUUUAGUGGAGACAGGGUUUCACUUGUUGGUCAGGCUGGUCUUGAACUCCUGACCUUAGGUGACCUGCCUACCUUGGCCGCCCAAAGUGCUGGGAUUACAGGCGUGAGCCACUGCAUCCGGCCCAACUAAUAUUCUUUCUUACUGGCAGUCUCCUAGUUAUAUAAGGAAAAAUAUGUUUUUGUGAAGUACUUUUGUAGCAUUUUUGUUUGCUUACACUUACUACUCAUUAGCUUUAUUUAUUCUGUUACCAAUAGUCAUCUUUAUCUUCUUUUACCUUCAUGAUUUUAUGUGUAGCUUUUUGGUAUCCAUUGUUCCUGUUGUGGAUAAAGCAAGGCGCUGCAUUAGAUAAUGAAAACCACUGCUUAUCUUCAGAACUUUCCAAUGGCUUUUUGUUAUGUUGUCUGCUCUGUGAAAUUCAGUAUCUUAAUCAGCAUACCGCAAUUUAGGAUUGCAAAACAGAAUAAUCCCUAACACCUGCCGUUUGAAUAACGUAUAGCAUCAGUGUAUAUAAUCAGAUAAUUGGGCUAUGUGCAGAUAUAAAUAUACGCUGAUGAUAUCAGCCUGUUGGAAAGAGGUUAGUGUUAAGAGACAUAUCCCUGUUCCUGUCUGGAUUCUCCAUCUUCCUUCUUCAUUGCAAUUGCUUUGGGUCUGUCACUUAACAGUUCCAUCCUUGGUACAACAUAGAGGUUAAGCAAGUUACUUAAUUACUUUAGACCACCAAAACAAAACAACAAAGUAGUAAUGGGAAGGGGUCAAAAGGCCUAGAGUAAAAGGAAAGUAAUGUGGUUUAACCAUAAUAAAUGUAAAUGAAUAUUAUUAUUUUAUUUAUAGUUAUAUUUCUUUAAUUAUUUUUUCCCAUAAGUGUAUGACCUUAAAGGAAAGUAUUUCUGACAGAGGACUGAGCCUGUAGAAGAUAAGCGCAGACUGAAAUUAUUUGAUUUUCAUCAAGCAGCUGAUGGUAUCCAGGAACAACAGAGACAAGAACAAGCAGGAAAAAAUUUGGGUACAACAAAAAAGGGCAUUGGCCCAGUUUAUUCGUCCAAAGCUGCUCGGAGUGGACUCAGGAUGUGCGACCUUGUUUCUGACUUUGAUGGCUUCUCUGAGAGGUUUAAAGUUCUAGCUAACCAAUACAAAUCUAUAUACCCCACUUUGGAAAUAGACAUUGAAGGUGAAUUACAAAAACUCAAGGGUUAUAUGGAAAAGAUUAAACCAAUGGUGAGAGAUGGAGUUUAUUUUCUAUAUGAGGCCCUACAUGGACCACCAAAGAAAAUCUUGGUAGAAGGUGCAAAUGCAGCACUAUUAGAUAUUGAUUUUGGGACUUACCCUUUUGUAACCUCUUCAAAUUGUACUGUUGGAGGUGUUUGUACUGGUUUGGGUAUGCCACCUCAAAAUGUUGGAGAAGUGUAUGGAGUUGUGAAAGCUUAUACAACUAGAGUUGGUAUUGGUGCCUUUCCUACAGAGCAAGACAAUGAAAUUGGAGAAUUAUUACAAACAAGGGGUAGAGAGUUUGGUGUAACUACUGGAAGGAAAAGAAGAUGUGGCUGGUUGGACCUCGUUUUGCUCAAAUAUGCUCAUAUGAUCAAUGGAUUUACUGCGUUGGCACUUACCAAGUUGGAUAUUUUGGACAUGUUUACGGAAAUCAAAGUUGGAGUUGCUUACAAGUUAGAUGGUGAAAUCAUACCUCAUAUCCCAGCAAACCAAGAAGUCUUAAAUAAAGUUGAAGUUCAAUAUAAGACUCUCCCAGGAUGGAACACAGACAUAUCAAAUGCAAGGGCGUUUAAAGAACUACCUGUUAAUGCACAAAACUAUGUUCGAUUUAUUGAAGAUGAGCUUCAAAUUCCAGUUAAGUGGAUUGGUGUUGGUAAAUCCAGAGAAUCUAUGAUUCAACUCUUUUAAUGAUUGCCAGUAAUGCAAGAAACACUCCUUGAGAGGGAGGGGAAAAGACUUUCUUAAAUAUUUCAUUUAUGACCUGCAAAUUCAAGAAUAAAGACACUGAAGUAAGUUUGAAGCCCUACAGUUGUUUCCAGUCUUUUCAGAUGGAUGCCUACUGUGGAGAUUAACUUUGGCAUAUUCCAGUGUCAGCUUUCUUUAGCUGGAAUUGCCAAAUCAUUUGUUGCUCCUGCUGCUCUCAUGGUGCCACGUUUUUUUUUUCAAUGUUUAGUAAUAGUAUAAUCCAUGUUGUUUGAUAUCAAAAGUAGAAUUACUUUUAAUGUAGUUUUUCUUCAUUAUUGUCAUUGCGUGUUCUUAAGUUUUACCCCUAUUAGAUGGUAAGAACAAUUAAUGCAGUUUUGCACAAAUAUUUUUACAUUCUGAUCAUUCAGUUCUGUCAUUGUAAUCUUUGUUGUUAGAAACAAAUGAUGAAAACAUAGGGGUUCUGUAAACUUUUGUAAUGCUAUGAAUUCUGUUUAAAUUUUGGGCUGUCUAUUUUCUGCUGAAACCAUGCAAAAUUGAGCUUUGGUGGGGCUGGGAGGGGGUUAUGUAUUCAUGGGACCUUUAAUUUGUACAGAACACAGAACUUAUUUCUGUCAGUUAUUUAAUACAUUGAAAAUUUAGUGAAAUGUUCAAAGAGAAUAGAUGUUUCCCAAAACAACAAUCUUUAUGUUAAAAAUAGUCAUUAAAAGAUCUGUUGUAAUAUAUGGUGGAUAUUUUUCUUUAAUUUCAAACAUUACCUCUGAAAUGUGUAUCUUUUCUUUUUUAUCUUACCAUUAAUUUUAAAUCUAGUGGAUUGGUUUUCAACAUCGUGCCUGCCGAUAUGCCUACAGAAUCAUCUGUAAGUGUCAAAAUGAACCCACGUUGUUAGCCAUAAUUUUGAUUAUGCCUUUAUUUCUCCUUUCUUGAAAAAAAAAAGGUGUUAUUUUGACAAUUAGGCAUAACAUUGUUUUGUAGAUUAUCUUUUAAUGAACUAUUUUAAAUGUUAAAUUAGGUGCCACUUAAAUUUAUUUUAUUACACCAUGAAUAGCUGAUUAAAAGAACCAAAUAUUUCUAGUA